AGAGACCAGCACUGCUGGCUGCACCAUGAAUGUGAUCUACCCACUGGCAGUCCCCAAGGGGCGCAGACUCUGCUGUGAGGUGUGCGAAGCCCCAGCCGAGCGGGUGUGCGCGGCCUGCACAGUCACUUAUUACUGUGGGGUGGUACAUCAGAAGGCUGACUGGGACAGCAUCCAUGAGAAAAUAUGUCAGCUCUUGAUUCCACUGCGCACUUCCAUGCCCUUCUACAAUUCAGAGGAAGAACGGCAGCAUGGCCUGCAGCAGCUGCAGCAGCGGCAGAAGUAUUUGAUUGAAUUCUGCUACACCAUAGCCCAGAAAUACCUCUUUGAAGGGAAACACGAAGAUGCUGUACCAGCAGCUUUGCAGUCCCUUCGCUUCCGUGUGAAGCUGUAUGGCCUGAGCUCCGUAGAGCUUGUGCCUGCUUACCUGCUGUUGGCCGAGGCCAGCCUUGGUCUGGGCCGAAUCGUUCAGGCUGAAGAAUAUCUAUUCCAAGCCCAGUGGACAGUCCUCAAAUCAACUGACUGUAGUAAUGCCACCCACUCUUUACUGCAUCGGAAUCUGGGACUUCUCUAUAUAGCUAAGAAAAACUAUGAAGAGGCCCGUUAUCAUCUGGCCAAUGAUAUUUAUUUUGCCAGUUGUGCAUUUGGAACAGAGGACAUUAGGACUUCAGGAGGCUACUUCCACCUGGCUAAUAUAUUCUAUGACCUUAAAAAGUUGGACCUGGCAGACACAUUGUACACCAAGGUCUCUGAGAUCUGGCAUGCAUAUUUGAACAAUCACUAUCAAGUCCUCUCACAGGCUCACAUCCAACAAAUGGAUUUACUGGGCAAACUAUUUGAGAAUGACACUGGCUUGGAUGAAGCCCAAGAAGCAGAAGCCAUUCGCAUCCUGACUUCAAUCUUGAACAUUCGAGAAUCUACAUCUGACAAAGCCCCCCAAAAAACCAUCUUUGUUCUGAAGAUCCUGGUCAUGUUUUACUACCUGAUGAUGAAUUCUUCAAAGGCACAGGAAUAUGGCAUGAGGGCCCUCAGUCUAGCCAAAGAACAACAGCUUGAUGUCCAUGAGCAAAGCACCAUUCAAGAGUUAUUAAGUCUCAUUUCAACUGAAGACCAUCCCAUUACUUAGUGACCCAUGAGCUCUGCAUCAAGGGUUAUUCCAGGGGCUACUGAAGAUCUAAUAUAUUCCAGCCUUGCACAACUGCUUUGAGGUACUGUAGACUGCUGAAGUUUCCACCCUCUUCCCCUGGGAUUGCACACAUAGCUGUUAUUUUUUUCUUACACAGCAUAUUAAGGGAAUAUAAAGCUUUAGGCAUAGAAAUCACUAAAAACUGUGUUUGUCAUGACCUUUGUACUUGAUUUAUCAUGACUUUGUAUGACUGAGUAAUAUGUAGUCAGAUCACUAAUAUGGUAUUUGUAAUUAAACUACAAAUAGUUUGUCAUUUCCCAGAAGUCUUCCAACGAUGCAUGUUUCAUACACUUUUGCUAAAGGAGGGGUAAAGGAGGGGGUAGGGAAUAAAGCUAUAUUGGAACAAA